CGGCUUUUCAAAAUUCAAUAGUCAUGUUAUUAGCAUUUAUUAUUUUCAGAGCAGAUUAGGUUUUUGUCAUCAGGCUUUUUUCCUUAUGCAUGAUAUUUAAUAAACCACUUUGUGGCCAGAAUAUAUAGGGUGAAAUAGAGUAGAGGGCAACUGAGGGAUUUUCUCCAAACAUAGCAGCAGGCAGUUGGGGAUUUAUGAGUUUAGGGGAGGGACCUCACUUGUUAGCUGUCCUUGGGAGCUCUGCCUAGUGGCCUGGCAAAGUAGCAAUUUUCCAAUGGCUUUGUGGAGACCGUCCAAACUCCUGGAACAUAUUAUUACCAGAGGGUUUUAUAGUCUUUUUUCAUUGUAGAUUUUAAAGGAAAAUGUAGUCUGAAUGCUAGAAUGGAGGAGUUAAAGGGACUGUAGAAAUCACAUAGUCCCAUCCCUCACUCAACAGAUGAGAAACUAAAGCCUGGAGAGAUUAAUGAAUUUCAUAGACACAACUCUGAGGCAGCUGGGGGCUACACUCAAGUAUCCUGACUGCCAAAAUCUAUUCACUCCCUUGCCCUAAUUCUUCCUACAGCCUUCACUUGUAUUCUUCCAGUUGAUUGAUGGAUUCAGCAGCACCUACUGAGUGUAUGCUGUACUCUGAAGCCCUGUUCCUGGUUCAGAGAUGGGGUCCCUGCCCUUCAGGACCCUAUAGCAUUGUCUUGGAGGAAACCAGCAUCUGAACAGAUCAUUGCCAUUCAAUGUGCUGUUCUAGGAGAGAAAUGGGCCGAGGAUGCUAGGGUAACAGGUAGGAUAGUAUAACUCACAACUGGAGGGGCUGGAGAGAGCUUCCCAGAGGAGGUGACAUUUGAGUUGGAACUUGAAGGAUAAAUCAGAGUUGUAGGGUAGAGAUGAAGUAGCAGUAUGUGCUGUGUGAGGGAGUGCCGUGUCUUCAGACAAAGAGGUCAUGAGGAUUUUUGUCUGGAAUGAGUGGCAAUAAUGCAGAGCACUGGUGGGCAAGGGUGUGGUAAGAAGUGACAGGAGAUAUGUUUGGACAGGGAAGUUGGGACCCGUUUGGUUGAGGUAUGUUUGGACAGGGAAGUUGAUGAUGACGGUCUCUGGGUGUCGUAUUAAGGAGUUUAGAAUGUAUCCAUAAGCAAUCGGGAAAAGCGGUGUUCUUAGGUAGGGAUGGUAAGUGGAUGUCUAACAGCUGAUUUUGGUGGCAGUGCAUGAAUUAGAGGAAAGGGAGCCCCACGCCACAAGGAGCUCCAGGGAUGCUUUCAGUAGUCCAGAUCAGAAUUGGUGAGGGUGGCCAAAGCUUGGGCAGGGAGAAUAGAGGAGCAUUAUGUGCUAAGAGAGGUAGGGAAAUAGAACUGACAGGGUUUAGGGAUUGGUUAGAUACAGAAAUUCUGGAAUAGGGAUGAUGGAAAUAAGGGAAUUACGAAUCAAACUCUCAGGAGAGAAAUUGGGUCUGAAGAUCACACUUUGGGAGUCAGAAAUGUUUAGAUGUUGCUGACAUUGAAGGAGGGGCAGGGAACAUGAACAGAAAAGACAUGUGGCCACUGCCUAUUAUUGGAUGUGUCAUUUUCAUGAAGGGCUUUAUUAUCUGUUUCUAAAUUGAACAAGCCAGGGUUUUCCCAAGCGACCUCAGUGGCUAUGUGCAGGACAUACCUUGGCUGUACAUCUUCUGAAAAAGGAGAGGCUGGAGGUUGGCAGAGGGAGAGUGGCCUGAUCUGCCACUGGCUUCCCAGCACUGACACAUUUCCCCACAUUAGACUGAGAAUGCCAGCUCAGAAGCAGCAUAACCAACUGUGAGAUCUUGGCCAGGCAGGAGAACGCAUUCUCCCUAAGUGGGCAUAACCGGACUCCUCCCAGGAAUCCAAGAUGGGAUCCAGGAGGCUCUUCUUCCCCCUUUAUAGCUCCUUGAUCAAAUCCCUGGUAUUUGCAUCACAGUGAUUUACCACAGUUGUUUAAAAUAAGCCAUGAUGUUAUUCCACCAUCAUACCAGAGUUUGGCUUAUUAUAUUUCACCCUUUUCCCUGAUAACUUAACUCAGCCUCUAGAGCUUGAUAGAGGGGAAGCUAUCCUGAAAUGAAAUCCCCUUCCUCUUCUUUGCUUUACUAUUUGUAAAGUAAUAUGUACAUACCGUGCAAUGCAUACAGUGGAUCACUUUGCCUUUUGUCAUUUGGUAAUAGGUGUGAUGUGAGGUGGGAGAAAUGGUCAGGGGAGGAGGGGAACACUUUUGGAGGUCAUUUUUCUCAAAGUUAUGACGUUAGAAAGAAGAAGAAAUGUGUGAGGGAUUUGAGCUGACUGCCAGGCUUGGCAGCUGGUUAAUAUGACGCAUCAAAUGUCUCAGGAGACGUAACAGACAGGCCAUUGAGGCUGGGUCCCAGAGCCACAAGGCCCCUUUGUGAACAGGGCCAUGGCUAGCCAGCAUGGCUCCAGUGGUGCAGCCCUUGGCUGACUGGGUAAACAAUAUUGCAUCCACACCAGCCCUGCUUCAGACACAUUUAACGUGGCCUGAACUCGAAGGAUUGGACCUGAAACUCAGCAGUGUGUCAUGUUCAACUUGCCUGUGACCCAGAAGACAAGUAGGGCCCCUUUCAUUUCACUGACACAUUAUCUUGUGCUUAAAGGGUUAUCUGUUUGUCAUUGAUCGUGAUGGUUUAGGAAGCUGCAGGCCAUUGUGUACAUACGUACAACCACAUAGACUCUUGGACUAGAAAGAGACGCCUCUGAUGGAGAUCAUGGAGUCCAUCUCCCUGGCUGGUGCCCAUACUGGUGGGCUCAGUAUGUAAUGAGUACUCAGUAGUUUGGUCCAACCCAUUACAUUGUUGAGACUUCACUCCUUUUUGCCUAGAGGUAGAAAGCUCCAAAGAGACAAGUGAUAGAACUUAUGAGAAGAAUAAGAAUUUGAGUUUUUUGUGAUCACUCUUGACUCACCAUAGCUUACAAAUUCUCUCACCUGCUCUGAUGCGCCCUAAAGAUGGAGAUGUCUGGUAGGUGAUUAUAAGGCCCUUUAGGCCCCUUUCCUGGGAACCCUCUGGGAGAUGAGGCCUUGACCUCGUUGACUUGACCCACCUUGGCCCAUGUGGGUGAGCUACUGUGGCUGGUGGGGAUGGGAGUGCUAAGGCAGCAGGGGCCUGCAGGGAACAUGUGUUGGCUAGGGAUGAAGGCUCUGGUUUUCCUCUUGUUCUACUAUACUUUUUCCUCAACCUGAAAGUGUAAAUGGAUAAGAAUGAGGACAAGAUGGGAAUUAAACAGGUUGUUACUGUGGAGAAUUGUGACCACUCCCAACCCCCCAAGCAAAGGCAAGCAUUUGGAUAUUACUUAUGACUCUUUGUGGAAACAGACCACUUCUAGAAGUAGUGACUUGGCUUAUGCAAUCUGCACUGUUAAUGGAAAUGAAUGCAUGAAUGAAUACCAAGGGAUGAUCUAAUUUUUAUCAAAGCAGUUUGGAGUAUAUUAGUCAACAUGCAUAUUUGUUUUCCAAAGAAAUCCAUAUUUCAAAACAUUUGGGAACUAGAGAUGCUAAAAAAAUUACUUAAAAUAUCCUACUUUCCUAAUACACCCACUAACAUUUUUCCUGUACAAAUUAAUUUUUUCACAUUAUAAUGAUAAAUUAUAUUGUUUAGUAUCCUCGCUUUUGAAAGAUAGCAUUGUAUCACAAGCUUUUUUCCACAAUCCUUUAUUUUUUCAAAACCAACAUUUUUAUUGCUGUAUAAUAUUUCAUAAAGUAUACCAUUUACACCAUUUUCUCCAUGAUAGAGCGAACAUCAUCAUGCAUAUCAAAUUAUCUAUGUUUUGGCUUCCUUAGGAAUCAUUAUUUAGAAAUGAAAUUAUUGGGUAAAUUAUAAUAAACAUUUAAAAGCUUCUGAUGCCAGAAAACCUUGUAAAAAUAUUACGGUGCCUGUUUUACUGCACUUUGACCAACGUUAGUUAUUACAUCAUUAUAAUUGCAAAAUCUUUGCUAAUUUAAUAGGCAAAUAGUGUUUUGUUGUUGUUGUCUUGAGAUGCCUGUCGCUCAGGCUGGAGUGCAGCAGUGCAGUCACAGCUCACUGCAACCUCUGCCUCCCAAGCUCAAGUGAUCCUCCCAUCAUAGUCUCCCCAGUAGCUGCGAUUACAGGCAUGUGCCACCGUGCCCAACUAUUUUUGUAAUUCUUUUUUGGUAGAGUUGGGGUUUCACUAUGUUGGCAAGGCUGGUCUUGAACUCCUGGGCUCAAGCAGUCUACUCACCUUGGCCUCCCAAAGUGUUAAGAUUACAGGUGAACACUGCACCCUGCCUGCAAAUAGUCUUAACUUCCUAUUUGAAUUUGUUAUAACUGGCUAGGUUAAUUUUGUGGGGAAGGGAGUAUGUUUUGCUAUUUAGACUUAGUUGAUCUCAAAAAUAGGCUUUUUGUGUUUCUUGUUCCUAAGACUUAUAUAUUAUAAUGGACUCAGCAUAAACUAAAAUCUGUUUUUUCUAACACUUGCUCUCAUUGUCCAUUUUCUAGAACUCUGUCUUCACCCUUAGCAGGUGAGAAUGGAGUAGUUGUGGUGGUGGUAGUCAUAGCAGGAGGGUGAAACCUUCACCGAAUGCUGACUGUGUGCCAGGCACUUUGUGUGGGUUACUUAUCUUCCUUAAUCUUUACAACUCUAAAGGGUGGGUACUAUUAUUAUCACAAUUUUUACAUACAAUAAAAACUUAGGCUUAGAGAGGGAGGUUAACUAACUUGAUCAAAGCCAGCAGCUUGCAAGUGCAGGAGCCAGGUGCAGACCUGGAAUGCUUUGCUGCACACUGCGUCUCCCACGAGUGUAAACACUUGGCCACUGUACUUUGCAGUGGAGCCGCAGAUUUAAGCUUUCACUUGGGGUCACUAAAUCUGGUGAAUUUCUAAUCAGAUUUAUAGAAUAUAUCACAUGUGAUGUCCAGCCUGUGCUCUGCCCACCUUCUGUUUUUUUCAACAGGACCAGAAUUCUGGUGAAGUAUUCUAGACUCUAGGAAGAAAGCUGUCUGGAUACCUCUUUUUCUUCAGAUAUCUGGGAAGACUGUCACAGACCAGACUUAAUGGGGCUGACAGCUGUGGGUGUGGGCUUUCGUCUGUCUUUUGGUUUGCUUUCAUUUGGAGGUGCUUUCAUUCCUAGGGUGAGGGUUGUGGGUUUUCUUUAGAUAUUUUUAUUAGAAUGUUUCCAUUAUGGAAGAUGAUGAAUACUAACUUAAGACUAAUUUGUAUGUUUUAGGCAGUAUCCAUUUGGAAAAAGACUAAGAAUGACUCCUGUCAAUGAAAAGAACACUUAAGGCUCUGUUUCUACUCUCUCAGCCUGUACAUUGCCUUUUUGGCCUUUAUCUUGGCUCAAUCUUGUCUGUUCAGCAUAGGGGAUUUGAUUUACUAGCUUCCGGGAAGUGGAGAGAAGAGUGGUAACUGUUUAUUAAUAUUUUGUUCAUCUAUGAGUACGUUAAUUUGAUUUUUUGGUAUGUAGAUAGAUAUUUUAUAAAAGCAUGACAUGGUAGUGUUUGGCCCAGCCCUCCCAUCCUAGGUUGAUGAAAAUAUAAGAUGAUGUCAAAGCCAGAGGAGCUGUGGAUUUCCUGUCGUAAAGCAGACUUCUUGCCUUGUCCCAGGACAGCCAUCACCACCACCUUCUUUCUCAUCAGGGCAGGGGGCUUGCAGUGUCAUACAUUAAGUGAGGGAACCUGUGGUAUGACCUAUUCCCCAAAUCACUAUUUUCCUUUAAAAAAAUGCAUUAUGCAUUUUCCCCCAGAAAACCUGAUUUCUUUUCAUUGAGGAUAGAGUCAGAGGCACUGACAUUCUCUGGGUACAUGCCCACUGACAGUGCAGGGAGGAGGGACAAGUAAAGUGGGGGCAGCCCAAGAGUACAUUUGGCAAAUUAAAGAUAACGCCUGUCCUCAGGGAACCCUGUCAGCCCAGCAGUGCAGCAAGUCCAGUCUAAACAUGAACAAGCAUGAAGAUAUUUGCUAAAUCACAGGCCUUACUCCUAGUGGGCUCUGUGUUUGGAAUGUGCCAUAUUACAAGAAAGAAGGUUUGAUGGUCCUGUCUUACUUUGUGUUGGACAUGGCUGGAGGAGGGAGGAGAAUCUUGGGAGUAAGUAUGUGUUUCCAAAAUGGGGAAUUAUGAUUUGCAGUUUAUGCAAUCAUGAAAAUGAAUUGCUUUGUGGGAUGAAAAGGUAAGCCAGACCCAUGGCUGUUGAAUUAAAAAUGAUGCAUUGCCCUUAACGAAAAUGAGGCCAUGGAGCCUUAUUUAAAUUCCACCAGCUAAACAUGUGUUUUGAAUACCAGCAUGGGAACUCAGGAGUUUCUCCGGUAUUUAGGCCGAAUUAUGGCUGGAUGAAGGAAAUAAAAUGCCCUGUGUGUCCUGACAAACGGCUCUGCAGCAUGGGUAUUUCAAGAAGCUAGGGUCAAGUUCAGGUUACUUUCUCAGGAAACCUAACAAUUCCAGCUGUAAUGUAUUAAAUGAGUGACUUCUGUAAACAGGAGGGUUAUCUGUAGCCACCCUGGAUAGCAAUGAUUUUGAUCUUAGUUUACCCAAGAGUAGAGUCUUCAUUUGAACAGUUAUGAGAUUUAAGGUGUCUACAUGACCAAAGGGGUCCAGGUGGGAAGUUACAUGAGUUUGGAAAAAAAAUUUCAGGGGGUUUGGGUUCUGGCUCUUCCUUCCGGUAGCAAAUUGCAUAAGUUCUCAGAGCCUCAGUUUCCUUAUCUGUGAAAUGUUACAGCUGAUUUUUUUUCCCUAAAACUAUUAGGUUGGUGCAAAAGUAAUUAUGGUUUUUGCCAUAAUAACUGAUUUUCUUCGUUCGAUAAAUAAAACAUAUUCAUUGCACAAAAUUUAGAAAUACAGAUAACUCCCAUUCCGCCCCCCAAAAGAAAGAAAAUAGAAAUUGCCUCAGUCUUAUUAUCCAGAGAUACCAUUGUUAAACCCUCUGUUCACUAUGUUGCUUCAAGGACUAGAAAAUUAUAAGAAAAUACUGUAAGUUGCAAAGCUCUAUAUAAAUAAGCGGUAUUUUUAUUGAGUCAACAGAAUUCAAAUUUGAACCUCUUCACAGCCAAGAAGCCCUAUAUUAUUUAACCUCAUUUUAAAUUUCAUUUUGUUUACAUUUUUUCUGAAUAUUAAAAUAACAAUGCUGAUUUUUUGGUUUAUCCAUGUUUUCUAAUUUUUCUAUAAUGUACAUGUAUUAUUUAGAUAAUAAAAUUUUUUUAAGUAGCCAUACAUGUUCAUUGUAGAAAAUGUGUAAAGAACAGAAAACUAUCAAGAGUAGAAGAAAAAUCCAUAGUCCCAUCACUUGCAGUAAUAGCUCCUUCCGGUCUUUUUUUCCUUUUGUAAUAGUUCCUUCCAGUCUUUUUUCUCUGCAUUAUUUUUUACAAAGGCAAAAGCCUAAUAUAUAUUAUAUCUUGAGAAAUUUGUUAAUAUUUCGCUAUGGAUGGCUACAAGUUAUGGAAGGUUGCAUAUGUCACUGUUACUGAUUAGAAGCAGCUGGCUCUUCAGAGGACUGACUCAGCCCUUUGAUAUGGAAUGUGGAUGAUUUGGGAUUUCAUGCUAAUGCUUAGUAUCUAAGCUGCAGUUCCCAGAUUGCGACCCAGUGGUUGAGAUCAACAGAAAAAUGAGUUUCCCAAGUCUUUGCAGAAGAGACACAGCUGUGGUUGGAGAACUACACAUCAAGACUUUGUUUGCUUUUGUGAAUGGCAAAUAAAUCUUGGGACCCCAAAAUCACUAAGCCAAAGGGAAAAGUCGAGCUGGAAACUGUAUCAGGCAAACCCGCCUCCUAUUUUAUUCUUAAAUAAGAUAGCUACAAAGACAAAACAAAACAAGAACAAAACAAAAAACUAUAUACUUUCCUCACAAUUUGCCCACAAGGAAAUUCCUUAUGGACAAAGGACAGACACAACUCAAAAUCAUCCCUCUGCUUACCUGAGAAAUACAUGUGAUUGCUUCCUCUGCCCUACUGUUUCACUAAGCAAGACUAAGGCAUAAGCGACUAUUCUUUUACCCUCCUCUCACAUGUAAAUUGUGUAUUCAGUUGAAUACUUGAGAAAUGUUUUGAUUUUAAUUUCUCUAUUAAUUUUGCAUAGGAAAAUGUCUAUUUAGCCCCCUGCAUUUUCUCUUUAUGAAUUACUUCACUACAUCCUUUUUCUAUUUACCCAUUGAUUUUUUUUCUUUUCCUGUCAUGUUUUGCAAAGUUUUUGUCAAACAAGCCAUUUUUUAUUACAUAUUAGCCUAAUAGCCCAAUUAUAAAGGAACAUAGAGUUUAAUAUAUUGAGUGUGGCUUGCUGAUCACCAUUCAUGCUUGAGAAUCUGGGGACCCCAGAGUGGGAACAGCUAGUCUGUUGCAUGAGUUGCUCUGAUGCUCACUGAAAUCUGGAACUGGCUCUCCAGAACCAGGCCUUCUAGGGUACAUGCACAAUGGUCUAGAGCAGCUCUCACUGUUCAAUAGAAAUGUAACAUGAGCCACAUAUCUCAUUAAACAUUUUCUAGCAGUGACAUCUUAAGUUUGAAAGAGACAAAUGAAAUUAAUUUUAAAGCAUAGUUUAGUUAACUCAUUUAGAAACAUUAAAAAAAUUUAGUUAACCCAUUAUAUCCAAAAUAUUGUCAUUUUAACAGGUAAUCAAUAUUAAAAACUCUCAGUGAGGUAUUUUCCUUUUCUACCAAGUCUCUAAAUUCUUUUCUUUCUUUCUUUUUUUUUUUUUUUUUUUUUUUGAGAUGGAGUCUCACUUUGUUGCCCAGGCUGGAGUGCAGUGGCUCGAUCUCAGCUCACUGCAACCUCUGCCUCCCGGGUUCAAGUGAUUCUCCUACCUCAGCCUCCCAAGUAGCUGGGACUACAGGUGCAUGCCACCACACCUGGCUAAUUUUUGUAUUUUUAGUAGAGAUGGAGUUUUACCAUGUUGAUCAGGCUGGUCUCGAACUCCUGACCUCAAGUGAUCCACCCACCUCGGCCUCCCAAAGUGUUGGGAUUACAAGCAUGAGCCACUGCGCCUGGCCCUAAGUCUUCAAGUUCUGAUGUCUGUUUUACCCUUAGAGUACAUCUCAGUUCAGACUAGCCACAUUUCAAGUACCCAAUAGCCUAGUGGUUAGUGGCCACUGUCUGGACAGUGUAGGACUAGAAGGAAUGUGAAUCUGUGUCUGAGAGUGUGUACUGACAUGCACUGACAUCAGUCCAGAACCAUGCUCUGGUUGUGCAUGGCAUUGCAUUCCGUGGUGCUGGAUCAUGCUGUGAUUCCUCACACGGGCUGUAGGGACAGGGACUGUGAUUCUUAGCUCAUGGUCUCCGAAGAGGAAGGGCAAUCCAAGGGUGGUGCUUCUUGCCUUUCUUCUAUCAUCCAUUAGCAGUGUGUGAUGAUAACAGAGGCUAACGAUUCAUAACUUUAUAGCCCUUAUGCCAAAUUUUUACAUCUAGCAGAGAUAAAUAUUAAGCCACUUUACCAAUGAAUCUAAACAAUAAUGUAUGUUGACAAUUCUGAAGCCAUUUCUAAUUACAUUUCACGAAUACUUUUAAAACUAGCUUAUUUAUUAAAAAUUUACUUAAGUCACAUAAACUUGAAAAAGCAUUUGGCUCAAAGUCUGUUUUUUUUCUGAUAAAGUGUUUGAUUUAAGCACUUUUUCCUUUAAGCCAAUUAAUUAGAGCUUUUAUGUAUUUUUAGUAGUGAAACAUAUACGUGACACAAAUACAUAGAUAUACUAGACACAUAGAAAUAGAUCUUAUAGAUUCAUAACACCUCUUUUUUUUCCUCCUAUUUUAGACUUCCAAUUUCUUGAUAACCUGUUUUAUUACUCCAGGCAGAUGUCAGCUACAUAGCCCUAAAUUUGCAUAUUAAAGGGCCAACUCUUGUGAAAAAUCAGAUAGUGAAAUUUAUAUCUCAAGGUACAGAGAGAAAGAGUCUGGUGGUACUACAGGGAGAUUAAAAAUGGAUGCCAAGUCAAACAUAAAAUUACAGAAAUCUAUCAUAGAAUUGUAUAAGGAAACCAAUUUUAUUUAGAUAGGUAGUUCUAAAUUUAGUCUCUGUCUUUUAACUGGAUCUGUGAACUCUGGGCAGAGCCCACACUGAAUCCUGGGUCUCCAAAAAGAGAACUAGUAUGGGGCUAGACCACGUGACGCUUUCAUAGUGCACUUUUUUUCAAACAAAGACAUUUCUCUAAGUGUCUAAACUACUCUCUUUCUUACUUUAAACACCCCAGAGUAAUCUCUGCUACAAUAACUAUUUUAGUCCAAAAAAAAAAAAAAAAGAAAAGAAAUGAGGUAUGAGGUAAUACACUAGUAAAGCAAGCAGUUUAAGAUCUGAGACAAACUUAUCUGUUUACACUCUUGGGGUUCCAUAAGGAAAAACAGAGGUUUCUCCCCAAAAGGGAGUCUGGUGCCUUCUUUGUUUUCUUUAAGGAAUCCUGGGCUAUUAGAAACUAUUUCAGGUCCCUUAUGCAGCAGAGUGUGGCAAGAGAAAGGAGAGAGAGCAGAAGUAAAUGGAGAAAACAGAAUUCAGUCAACUGAGAAGAGAAAAAAACUUUUUCUCAAAAAAAAAAGAAAGAUCCUAGGAGAGAAAAAUAAAAGACACACACACACACACACACACACACACACACACACACGCGUACACACACAUAUCUUGGAUAUUAGCUUUUAAUUGACUGCUAACCAUUGAGCUACUUAAGAAAAAAAAAUUUUAAGUCUCAUUACCAUAUUUUAGCUAAAACAAAUUGCUGAUAUUUCAAAACUAAUACAAAUGUCAAACCAGAAAGAGCCUGAUUUAGGAACCAAUCCCAGGCUAUCGUGGUGACAAAAAAUUGGGGGCAGAACCUUAGCUACCUUUAGCUACUGAACUGCAGCAUGGGGCAACAGCCAUUGCUACUUCAGUUUGGCUUGGCUUGUUACAUAAAUAAAGGUGCCCUUGUUAUGUAAAUAAAGCCCCUCAAGUGGUCAAAAUCAAAAAUCUUUCAGGCCUGCUGAAAGUGCUGUAAUCCCAGCACUUUGGGAGGCUGCAGCAGGUGGAAUGGCUGAGGUCAGGGGUUCGAGACCACCCUGGCUAACAUGGUGAAACCCCGUCUCUACUAAAAAUACAAAAAAAUUAGCUGGGUGUGGUGGUGCACGCCUGUAGUCCCAGCCGCUCGGGAGGCUGAGGCAGGAGAAUCCCUUGAACCCAGGAGGUGGAGGUUGCAGUAAGUCAAGAUUAAUGCCACUGCACUCCAGCCUGGGCGACAGAGCAAGACUCUGCCUCCGAGAAAAAAAAAAUUCUUUUUUUUACCUUUUGCUGGCUGUCAUUUUCCUUUUCCCAUUUUUUUUUUUCAGAUGUGGGAAUUUAGCCAAUUCAGAGGCCUUGUUCCCCAUAAUUUGAAACUUUCCCUUGGAUUUGAUCAAGUCAGAUAGAGCUGGUCAAACCCAAUAGGAAACAGAUGGAAACAACAACAGAAACAAACAAGCAACAACAACAACAAAACAGUUAUGCAAAACAAACAAUCUCACAAUUUAUACAAUUACUGAGCACUUUAAAGUUAAGGAGAAAUUAAGACCAGCUGGUUGUUAAGUUUAGCCAAGACAAAACCCCAAUUCAGCUACUUACCUAGGAGUGGGGCUCAGGCUAAUGACUGCUCUCUACCAUCCUAUAAACAGGAAAAAAACUCUAACUUGCCUUCCCUGUUGGAAGCAAGCUAAAACUCCAGAAAGGAGUUACCUGCACUCCAUCAUGCAGAAAAACUUGUCUUCCUUGUUGGAAGAAAGCAAAACUCCAGAAAAGGAGCUGUACAGCAAAAUAAACUUUAGAUCUCGAUCACAUUUGGGGAAAUCAGGGAUUCUCCGGAGGGGAAGUUGCCAGGCCUCAGCAAAUUGUCCUAUUGAUCCGAGCCUUAAAGGUAUCUUAAGCUGCUACGAAGCACCCAUAGAUUUGUCAAAGUACAGGGGAACCACCACUCAGAAUCCCUUCAGGUUUCCAAUUUGUGAACCCCAAAGUAUCUGAGACAGAUCUCAGGAAGUUUAUUUUGUCAAGCUUAAGAAUGCACCCAUGACACAGCCAAUGAAUGUAAGGUGUAUAUUGGUUUGGUCCAGAAGGGCAGGACAACUUGAGGUGGGGGAGGGGGCUUCCACAUUAUGGGUAGAUAAGAGACAAUCUGUUGCAUUAUUUAGAGUCUCUGAUUAGCUUUCAACUGAAUACACAAUUUACAUGUGAGAGGAGGGUAAAAGAAUAGUCGCUUAUGCCUUAGUCUUGCUUAGUGAAACAGUAGGGCAGAGGAAGCAAUCACAUGUAUUUCUCAGGUAAGCAGAGGGAUGAUUUUGAGUUGUGUCUGUCCUUUGUCCAUAAGGAAUUUCCUUGUGGGCAAAUUGUGAGGAAAGUAUAUAGUUUUUUGUUUUGUUUUGUUUUGUUUUGUCUUUGUAGCUAUCUUAUUUAAGAAUAAAAUAGGAGGCGGGUUUGCCUGAUACAGUUUCCAGCUCGACUUUUCCCUUUGGCUUAGUGAUUUUGGGGUCCCAAGAUUUAUUUGCCAUUCACAAAAGCAAACAAAGUCUUGAUGUGUAGUUCUCCAACCACAGCUGUGUCUCUUCUGCAAAGACUUGGGAAACUCAUUUUUCUGUUGAUCUCAACCACUGGGUCGCAAUCUGGGAACUGCAGCUUAGAUACUAAGCAUUAGCAUGAAAUCCCAAAUCAUCCACAUUCCAUAUCAAAGGGCUGAGUCAGUCCUCUGAAGAGCCAGCUGCUUCUAAUCAGUAACAGUGACAUAUGCAACCUUCCAUAACUUGUAGCCAUCCAUAGCGAAAGCUCUCAGAGCUACCCCCAUUCUCCGCAGGAGGUCACCUAGCCUUAUAUUUUCCUUUUAAGUAUGUUUGCUGAAAUGUUUGUGAGCCUGUCAGCCUCUGUAGCUCUCAUUUUGUAAGUAUUUCUCAUAGCCAGGUUUCCUCUGAAUGCCAACUCCUAACAGCUGAAUGUCAAACUCUAGAAGACAAUUUGACAAGGAUCACUUCAGCCCUCCCUACAUGGAUACGCAGACCUUCAUAGAGAUGGCCUCAGAAUAAGUCCAGCAGAUCCUAACAGAAUAAUUAGCCUCAGGCCUUGCUUGGUAACUGAACUCAAGACACUCCAUCUGGGCUCAGGAUGUGUUUCCCAGCUGGAUUUCCUUAGGCCUUCAAUUUAGCAGCCCUCCCAUUUCAUGUUGAAAUAACUGGGAUCAACGUUCCCCAGGCAAGGUAAAGAACUGGAGAGCUCAGUGCAAUUCUUUAUUCCAUAAGUGACUUCACCUUGCAACCAUCCGCAGUUUUCAGAAAGGAAUGUUAUCAGUGGGCACACCUAAACCAUCCCUCCCCUCUCUCGCUACACACCCACUGCAUAACCUGCCAUCUCUUUAGACACAAAGCAUUUCUGCAUCUUGGUGAAUUUGUGCCCCUUCCACACUGAAGUGCGUGUGAAUAUACAUGUCGUCCCAUGUGUACAAGGAAGUCCAACUCCACCACAAGAGUGAAAUUCACAAUGCCCUGCUUUCACCCCAGGUCACAGGAGCUUCGAUCAGGAAUGGACCCAAAACACUACACAUCUGUCACUGAGUCAGUGCUUCCUGCAGGCUGGCUAAAUCCUACAAUAAUACAUUUUUCAGGGAAAAGAGGUUCUCUUGGUAAGAGCCAAAAUGCCACAGAUUACACCACUGCUUUUGAAUGAAAGGGCAGAAACCCAUUCCCACCUCCUGAGUAUUCCCUUUCACACUUCACUUAAUGUGAAGAGGAAACGCAGCUGUCUCCUACAGGCUGAGGGGCACAGAUGAGUCUACAACUCCCUCCCCUUCUACUCAGGUAGCUUCGGGUGGGGCUUCUAUCUUUUAACAUUUAUUUAACUCUGGGAUUUGGAAGUCACUUAUGGUCAAUGGGAGCUUAUCUUCUCCAUCAUCUUUUUAUGUCAGGUAGCAAUUACAAGGAAAACCAAGGAGAGAGGCUGAAAUCAGGUGAUAGUGCUUUCUUGAUGCCAGCAUACGUCAUCAGUGAUGGUGACUAGUUACCUGAAUGACAGUGCAGAAAAGGCAGGUUUGCCAAGCUUAAGGGACAGGAAAGAAUGGGCUUUUUCAAAAUGGGAAAUUUUCUAUCAAACAGAGAGCACUGGCCUCACAAAUAACUCAGUUACGCAUUCAUGCUAAUAAAUACCACAUUACGAUGGACAAUGUGCAGGCAGGAGAGAAACUUCUAUUCCUUGGCUCCACUGCUCAGCCAGCUGGGGUGAGUGAGCUCAAAGGUCUGUACAAGCAGAUCUGAGCUUAGUGUAAACGAGGGAGAAGGAGUGUCAGAAGGGAACAGGACAAUUUCACAGAAAAUCAUACCAGUGCUAUGAAACAGCCUAUCCUCGGCUUGCAAAGAUAAUGUUAUUGAUGGGCCCCUAUUACGAUAAACACGUGCAAGUAAUGGGGACACAAAGAAAAGGGGAAAAGAGAGGAUGGGAGCCCACACUUACUGAUAAACUACUUGUGACUAUAACUCCAUGUUCUAAUUGUCUAUUUGUGAGCCUGUUUCCCUAUUAGAUUGUGAAAUCAGAGAGGAAGCUUACUAGACAUCCUGUAUCUCCGUUUCAUGGGACUAUAAUGCCACUUAUUCAGUUGUCAGAGUCUGAUACAUAGUAAGCACUGCAUAAAUGUUAGAUAUUCUCACCAUGAUUAUAAUUAUUAUCAUUGUAUCCCACACCCCCUAAUACAGAGCUUAGCACUGGGCAUUCAUGAGAAGCCUGGUAAAUUUUUUCUAUUACAGCAAACAUUUAUUGAACACUUUUUACAAUCCAGCCACCAGAAAAAAGUAGACUUUGAGCCAAAUGCUUUUUCAAGUUUAUGUGACUUAAGUAAAUUUUUAAUAAAUAAGCUAGUUUUAAAAGUAUUCAUGAAAUGUAAUUAGAAAUGGCUUCAGAAUUGUCAACAUAAAUUAUCGUUUAGAUUCAUUGGUAAAGUGGCUUAAUAUUUAUCUCUGCUAGAUGUAAAAAUGUGGCAUGAGGGCUAUAAAGUUAUAAAUGUAGCACAAAAGAAAAUUAUCUUUUUUUAUGUAAACUUUGAUAAAUAAGGAAUUCAGUAUUGUUCAGUUAAUGAAAACAGCUAAAUCCUGAGUUAUUGGCAAAAACAAACAAAAAAAAAAUUUGUCUAAUGUUAAGGUUCUUAGGAAAACCUGAACUCCACAGGUUAUAAAAUGGUUAACAUUUUUAAUGAUAACUAUCACAGUUUUAAUAAGUAAUCUGGUUGAAAAAACAAUUAGUUAGAUAAAUGUAGUGGAAUAAAUGCCUAUAAAUAAACUUAUCAUAUAAUUUAAAAUCUAAAGUUACAUAAUACGUAUUCAUUGAAUGUCUGGGUCAUUUCCAAUUUUUAAAUAAAUUAUAGAAAAAUGUUUUUCUAUAAAAGAAAUGUGUUCUUAUUUAAAGGAAAAUAAUAUUUGUCUCAUUCAAAGUUUAUUUAAAAGUUAUUUAUAAAACAAGGUAAUGGUAACCAGUAUAUAAAAGCAUUGUAAAGAAAAUUAUAAAUAUAAAAAGGUAUUUUUGGCAAGAAAGGUUAAAAAGGAAAAUAAUUUUAUAUGAGAAAGAAUCUUGUAUGGUAAAUUUUUUUCCUAGAAUAAAAUGACUGGUUAAGAAAGAGGGAUAUUCAGGACAAACCAGAAAGUCCACGUAUGCCAUGAAUGGUCUGUGUAAGUCAUAAUAAGGUUUGUAAAAGUAAAGUUUUAUGGGGGAAGAAAAACUUUAUAUGAUCAAGUUGUCUGUAAUGAAAGAGAAAUUAUUUAUAAUGGUCUUUCUAGAGAUUGUGUUUUGAUAUUUUAAAAAAACACUUAUGCACUAAAGAAUUGGGUAGUACAAUGAAACUUUUUUUAAGAUAUUGAUUUACCCUUAACAAAAUUACAAGACAUUUUAAUUUUUUAACCCAAAGUUUAACUUUUAUUGUAUCUUGCUGUUUCAGCUUCCUCUCCCCUUUUAAAAGCCCCGAAAUAGUAAAUAUCUCCUUCAACUCACUUUUGGCUCCCGUAAGUUUUAUUCCUCGGGUGCUGUUUGUUUGUUGUGGCCUUACACUAAAAAUGUUUUAUCCUAAAGGCCUAAAGGAAAUGUCUUCUCCAGCAUAACAUUCUGUGCUCUUGGCUUUAGAUGGUUCUGUGAAUCUAAAAAUUUUUACUUGUUACCUAAGAAACACUCUUCCUAUGUCUAAUUGAAGUACGCUUUUUAUUAGUUUGACUUUCAGGUUAUUGAUAAUAAAUGGAUACCCCACAGGGAAUAGCAGUGGCACUGCAGAAGAUCUUUUCUUUUGCCUUUUGGUAACUGGCCUAACAAACACAUUUUAUAUUUUAUUGAAAUAAUUCCUUUGCCAUUGUUAUUAAGUUUUGGUUUGCUUAGAAAAAACUGAGAUUAAAUUUUUUUUUUAAUUAAAGUUAUCACAUCUGUGUAACUUUCUAUAUUUUGCUUUUAAAGUCCUUGUGUCAUUAAGUUAUAGAGCUUUGACUUCUGGGGCUAAACAGGACACCAAGUCCUCUUCAGUCUUAAACCCUGACAGCAGUUAAAACCUCAUCUUCAGAUCCGGUAGAAGAUGCCAACCAAAAUAAACUGUGUUUGUGAGACACAGGGCCAGAAAUUAAAACUAUCCAACUCCUCAAGACCCAGAGACUAUUGUGGAAGAGGUGGGCAUGAGAUUGUAAGGGCCAAUGUUGAGAGAUAAAAUUAGUUCAGUUUCUCUAUAAAGUAACCAUUAAUACCAAACGCACACUGAUGCAAGACCAGCAUAUGAGCCUCUGUGUCAGAUGAACACAAUUUUUUUGGAGCAUUAACUCACUCCUUAAUAAAAGGUUAUAAAGAUUAUAAAAAGAUUUAUGGAAAUUAUAUCUUAUGGUCAAGAUAAUUAAAAUUUAAUAAAUUUACUUACAGAAUUUUAAAAGACACAUUUAAUUGGCCUCAUGCUGUCUUUAUUAGGGCUUGUUGUUUGGGAAGUUAAAUUGCUCUCAAAGAAUAAAGGUUUAUGCUUUUUUUUUUGGAAAUCGUUGAGUUAUCAUUUGGGCUAAAUGAUUGACUUAUUUUAUAACAACUUGUGAUCCUGUUUUGUGAUAUGAAGUGUUUUAAACUUUUUAUAUUUGACACACUUUCUGAAAUCAAAUUUUAACUUCAGUCCUCAUUAAUCUUUUGAUAUUUGGUCCCUUGAAGUCCAAAAAAGACAUAUUCAGCUUAUUUGAUGUAAUAAAAUCAUACAGGAAGUAGUGUCAAAUAUGAAAUGGGGUUUAUCCUUCUUUGGAUUAUAUUUAUAUAAAUGUGUUAUUAGUAUGUGUUCCAGAAUUGUAUGAGAUUCCUGUGAGCCUAAUAUAUCUUAGUAAAUGUUAUCAGUAGUAAUGGUGAUUCUGAUAUAAAAUUGUAUGCCAUAGAAGUAACCCAAUUUCCUUGUCAUUUGCAUCUUUAACCAUAACUUUUGUCAUCUAGUUGUUUCACUUUUAUUCUUUUCAAAAGGUGUUUUUUAUAAUCAGCUAUAGGACUCUGACAGUUGUUCUUGAAUGCAGGUUUCUGAUAACUUUGGAGACUGUGACACUAGAAUAGAGGAAAAACUUGCAAGACUCCCAUAGAAAGCUAAUGUGUUCAUAAACAUCGAGCAGAACAUGACUUAAUUACGUAGACUAAUGAAAGACUGAAAUAAUCUUUUUUAUGACUUUGUUUGGAAUGUUGCUAAUUCUUUUGUUUCUGCAUCUAGAAAACCCUUUUUCUUUGAGCUGUUUACAGCUUUUAAUAAUUGGGGCAGCUACACUCCUGUGAGCAAAAUCUGAAGCAUAUAUCUCUCUACCUGAUUUCUCCAGAAUUUGAAAACUAUUUGCAAGUAUAUUUAAUUUAUAGCAGUAUAGUUAUUUGCAUAAGUUCAAUAAGAAUCUUUUUCUUUGUAAUAGGACACAAUUGGAGACACUGGUUAUUUUACCAAGGCUUUCAUUGGAAUGGCAUACUUUUAGAUAGAACCAGAUUGCUUUAAGGAAUUGAGGUUGACUUGUAGAGCCAAAUAAAACCCUUUGGGAAAGCUGGCCUUAUACCAUGUCUACACAGUCCCUGUACAGGUUCCUGACCUGCAGUAAGUAAAGAAUGUCACUUUCUGACAGGCCCAGGAGCCCUAAGUUUUCUUGGGCCCUUGAGGUGAGGAAUUCACCCAAUUAGUACAGGUAUUUGCAGGCACAGGCUGAGCUCAAAGCAUUGAAGUCUAAUCUGAGUUUCCUUGUGGAAUAAAGUUGCAGUAAAGCCAAUUAAAAAGAAAACAGCCUAUAUGGCAAAUAAUUUUUUUUUGCUGACUUUAUGCAAAUACUCAGGCCAAGUAUAGUAAGACCAACAGUUAUUUUACACAUAAAUUUGUCUUGUGAUUUGUCUUUAGUGAAAAUGGGGACUGGAGAGAGAAAAAUUAUGUUUCAAAAUAAACUAGACUACACCUGUUAUUAGAUUCUAGUCUUGUCUAAUGUUUUUCAAUGUUUAUUAUUUUCUAUAGUUUGGACUGAAUUCUAAAGUUUUUCCUGGCUACACGUCUCCAAAGUAAUGUUUUUAAUUGAUUUUUUCUUUCUUUCCUGUCCUAUUUUCCCUCCAUUUUUUUCUUGAUUUAAAAUCCCUAAAAAUGAAGCUGUGCUUUCUUAAAGCCCUGCAAACUGAAGCUAGACAACUUAAGCUACAGAAGAAAAUAACAGCAACUUAUUUACAUAUAUAAACCACUUUCAUACCUGCCUAUUGAUGUGUGGACUUCAGAUAAUAUGGCCUAUAUCAAUUUUCCGGGAUUGUUCUUCAUCUUUUUUGUUUGUUUUUUUCUCUUCCUCCUCCUAUUUUCUCUUCAUAGGAUAUGAGAUUUCACAACCUACUAAAAAUGAUCUUUCCUAAUAACCUGACACCUACCUUUCUAGGAGUAAACUGUCCUAGUUAUGAGAGAUCAGACAAAACCUGAGACCAGAGGCUCAUUCAUUUUCUUAUAAAAUGCUUUUUUGGAAAGAUGUGAAAGCAAAAUAAAUCUCAGAACCCCGAAAUCAGUAAGCCAAAGGGAAAAGUCAAGCUGGGAACUGCAUCAGGCAAACCUGCCUCACAUUUUAUUCUUAAAUAAGAUAGCUACAAAAAUAUAAAAAAGCCACAUACCUGCCUCACAAUUUCCCCACAAGGAAACUCCUUGUGGACAUAGGACAGACACAACACAAAGUCAUCCCUCUGCUUACCUGAGACAAAUGCAUAUGUGAUUAGUUCCUCUGCCCUAUUUUUUUACUAAGCCAGACUAAGGUGUAAGUGACUAUUCUUUUACCCUCCUCUCACACGUAAAUUGUGUAUUCAGUGAAAAGCUAAUCAGAGACUCAAAAUAAUGCAACCAAUUGUCUCUUUAUCUACCUAUGACCUAGAAGCCCCUUCCCCCACUUGGAGUUGUCCAGCCUUUCCAGACCAAACCAAUGUUCAUCUUACAUACUGAUUGACGUCUCGUGUCUCUCAUGUCUCCCUAACGUGUAUGUAACCAAGCUGUACCCAGACCACCUUGGGUAGAUGUGGUCAUGACCUCCUGAGGCUGUGUCAUGGGCACAUUCUUAACCUUGCAAAAUAAACUUUCUAAAUUGAUUGAGAUCUGUCUCAGAUACUUUUUGGUUCAUACCCUUUAUAUUUCUAAAUGUUGUUAGGAGCCCUUGGCUUAGGUUGAAAGAAAAUACAGUGAUUCUUAGGAAACAGGUUAACUGAAUAGUUAGGAUGGACUUGUUAGGAAUGGGGACGGGGAUGGAAAUUCAUGAUCUCAAAGAUAGGAGCUAAUACUAGGUAUUUGAGCUAUGAAGGGACACCCUUAUGUGUUCUUUUUGACAUGGCUAAAGUUAGACUCUUGAGCUCUAGACCUCCCUUACCUCAGCAAAACAAAUCAGUUUCUCCCCAAGACUUCCCACUUCAUUAAAUGGUGCCCCUAUCAAUUUGUGUAGAGCCCAAAAUCUAGGAGUAAUUUUUAAUUUUCCCGACUUCCCUUCUCCCCAUCCAUGAUAUAUACAAAAUGAAUCCCAAUUUCUGAGUGUUUCUCUUCUGCCACUACUCUGAGCUCUCCUCAGUUCUCACCUAGACCACACCUGGGCCUCAUUGGACUCCACACGAGUGUUCCUGCCACCAUGCACUGCAUUCUGUGCACACCACAGGAGAGGCAGCUCCUCCCCUGGCCUCUGUACACUCCAAGCCGCCCAUGCCAACUUCCGUUCCCAUCAACCAUGCAGCAGCACAGCCCCAUGUCCUCCCAGACCUCUUCCGCCAGCGGGCCACUGCACUCUGUCUCCCUGCCGCUUCCACUCCCGAUGGCCCUGGGUGCUCCACAGCCCCCGCCUGCCGCCUCCCCCAGCCAGCAGCUUGGUCCAGAUGCCUUUGCGAUUGUGGAGCGAGCCCAGCAAAUGGUGGAGAUAUUAACAGAGGAGAACCGGGUGCUUCACCAGGAACUUCAGGGUUACUACGACAAUGCCGACAAGCUCCACAAGUUUGAAAAAGAACUUCAGAGAAUUUCGGAAGCCUAUGAAAGUCUGGUCAAGUCUACCACCAAGCGAGAAUCGCUGGACAAGGCCAUGAGAAACAAAUUGGAAGGCGAGAUUAGAAGACUUCAUGAUUUCAACAGAGACCUCCGAGAUCGACUAGAGACUGCUAACAGGCAACUAUCCAGCAGGGAAUACGAAGGGCAUGAAGACAAAGCUGCAGAGGGGCAUUAUGCUUCCCAGAACAAAGAAUUCUUGAAGGAAAAGGAGAAAUUAGAAAUGGAGUUAGCAGCAGUGCGGACUGCAAGUGAGGACCAUCGGAGACACAUCGAGAUCCUGGACCAGGCUUUGAGCAACGCCCAGGCCAGGGUCAUCAAGCUGGAAGAGGAGUUACGAGAGAAGCAAGCAUAUGUUGAGAAAGUUGAGAAGCUGCAGCAGGCCCUGACCCAGCUGCAGUCUGCAUGUGAGAAGCGAGAACAGAUGGAGCGGAGACUGCGGACUUGGCUGGAGAGAGAGCUGGAUGCACUGAGAACCCAGCAGAAACAUGGAAAUGGCCAGCCAGCCAACAUGCCGGAAUACAAUGCCCCAGCCCUCCUGGAACUUGUGCGGGAGAAGGAGGAGCGGAUCCUGGCCCUGGAGGCCGACAUGACAAAGUGGGAGCAGAAGUACCUGGAGGAGAGCACCAUCCGACACUUUGCCAUGAAUGCCGCAGCCACUGCAGCAGCUGAGAGGGACACCACGAUCAUCAACCACUCACGGAAUGGCAGCUACGGAGAGAGCUCGCUGGAGGCCCACAUCUGGCAAGAGGAGGAGGAGGUGGUGCAGGCCAACAGAAGGUGUCAGGACAUGGAAUACACUAUUAAAAAUCUCCAUGCCAAAAUCAUAGAGAAAGAUGCUAUGAUUAAGGUCCUGCAGCAGCGAUCUCGUAAAGAUGCCGGGAAGACAGACUCCUCCAGCCUACGUCCUGCCCGCUCCGUUCCAUCCAUAGCAGCAGCUACUGGGACACACUCUCGCCAGACCUCUCUUACCAGCAGCCAGCUGGCUGAGGAAAAGAAGGAAGAGAAGACCUGGAAGGGGAGCAUAGGAUUGCUGCUGGGGAAGGAGCACCAUGAGCAUGCCUCUGCCCCACUGCUGCCACCCCCACCCACCUCAGCACUGUCCUCCAUAGCCUCCACUACGGCAGCCAGCAGUGCCCACGCCAAGACAGGCAGCAAGGACAGCAGCACACAGACUGACAAGAGUGCCGAGCUCUUCUGGCCCAGCAUGGCCUCCCUUCCCAGCCGCGGCCGGCUGAGCACGACCCCUGCUCACAGCCCCGUCCUGAAACACCCAGCGGCCAAAGGGACCGCAGAGAAACUGGAGAACUCUCCUGGCCAUGGGAAGUCGCCUGACCACAGAGGCCGGGUCAGCAGCUUGCUGCACAAGCCCGAGUUCCCUGAUGGAGAGAUGAUGGAAGUCCUCAUCUAACUGCCAUCCCUGUGGAAUUUCAGUACAGAACACUGACAAACAAGGAAAGCGGCAGAGAAAGAAGAAAGACCUAGAAGGUUGUAGAUGGGAAAUCAGGAAUGAUUUGAACUGAUAAAGAUUUCAGACUCAUAAGAACACAUUUUAUAAAUGUUAAACACAAAAACUACAUGACUGAAGAUAGAAGAGAAUGCGAUGGAUUUUAUUACACAUGGUGGAAGAGAGAAGAGGCGUGUAGGUUUGCAAACAAAGUUAAGAAAUAGGAAACUGAAUUUUUCAUUGUACAGAAAAUGUAUCUCUUGGGGAGGGCCUGUGUACCCCCAUUCUCUGAUUAUAAACAGAUAAACCCAAAUGUGGAUCAUCCUUGGAAUACCCCCAUUCUCCUUGCCUCUUAGCAUGUUUGAUUUAAGAAAAGCCUCCAGGAAAUCUUGAGAGCCUGUCUUGGCAUAAUGCAGUGUCACCUGUGCCAACCAUGGGGUGUCCCGUGAGUGUGAGUGUGGCAGUGAGAAGAAGCAUCGAGGGCGAGGGGAAUAUGAAAGUUGGUCUUCACCUAAUUACCUGUUUGGUUUGGAUUUUCAAGAGAUGAUUGGGCUUCUUAGCUUUUCUGAAUUCUGCAGUAUUUUCUAAACAGGAUAGAUUAUGAUCUCGGUCCCCAUCCAUCCUAACUUCUGAGUUCAUCUCUGUCUCUGCUUUACAGUCUUUAAUUUUUUGUUGUUCCUUCAUUUUUUUCUUUUUAAUAAGACAUAGCAGAAUUCCUUAGGUAUGGGAUUUAUGAGACCAGUACCUGAACUGUCAUCAUUCCUACUGUGUUUGAUAGUGACCAGUAGGACAAAGCCACGUGCCGACUUCCUGGCUGCUUCACCUUUGCAUAGCUGGGUUGCAGCUGCGAACCUCAUUCUGACUGUGAACUAAGCAAGCUUUGAGGAGGCAGGAGAUUCCGUGGGUCCCUGUGACAUAUUGCAUUAAGAUCGUGGCACUUGCUUUUUUGUCUUUCACAUCGGCUGUCUUGCAAGGAGCUUGACAUUUCCAAAUUCCAUUGCUCUGUUUGGGGAAGACUUAGGACAGCACUCCAGGAAACAGAUGACAAUUUACAGACAGUUGUCUCAGUGGUUUCCAGAAUCUCACCAGCCUCCCGUAUAGCUUCUUGUAUUGAGGCUCAUGAGCGUAUUCACACUCUUUCCUCCCCCGCGCACGCCUCUGCUUGCUCUCGAUCAGCAUCCAGACCUCCGUGGCACCAGGUUGCCUCUGUUGUGAACUUCUUUUGUAACCUACCAGGCCAGUUGUAUAUACAGUGUUGUCAGGUUUUUCCGGGUUUCAGUUUUGAGGCAGUUUAUUCAAAGUGAGACAGAAGUGCCACGGAAAAGAGGCAGGAGUGUGUUAGGUGGUGGGUCCAUUAGACCUCUGCUGUGACAUUGCAUAUUCAGCUCUGCAGACACUGGCUUCCUUUACAAAUCUAAGAGAUGCUGGAUUAGAAAAGAGGAGAAGCUCAUCGGGCCAUCAGAGAGAUGCUCCUACAGGGUCCUGAUGUUUUUGUACCUCCAGGUCAGCUGGAUCGCUGUUUUCCCAGUUCCCUUUGCUCAUGCUUACUUAGAGGAAGAAAGAAAGGGGGGUACCUCUUCCAAGUACCUUCUAAAUGAAACACUCAAGAGAGUGCUACUCAGGAAACUUUGCUUGGAUCCUAAAAUGGACUGGUCUUGGGUGUGUAACCCCGGUGAAGUUAUAGCCUCCCCAAAUUGAGGUGACAGAAGGAAGACAAGAGGUGUAAGCUGGAGAGGGAAGGGAAGAAAUCAGUGGCUUUGGCCAGCCUCUGUGCCACCCAGUACGACAGAGGAGUGGGAACUGGCCCUCUGGGGCUCUGCUUGGCCAUAGGCACUGCACAUUGUGCCACCUGCUCAUCACCUCCUCUAGUCUCACACUGAGCAUCGGAGUACCUGUUGUGCAGACAGGAAAACUGAGGAGCUCUGAGAGGCUGAGCAUGGAGCUCACCCCAUGCCAUAGGGUGUGGGAAGAGGGCACAGGAGGCCUCAUCCAUGGGGGAAAGGGUUGAGGAUGGACAUGGGUGGGGAGAGGGCAUAGACAUCCCUUCCUAAUCUCUGUUCCCACCACAUUUCAUAGGAGAUGAGUUAGGAGAUGACAGCUAACUCUCUUAAGGACAUUUUGACCCCAGUUUAUGUUGGGGAUGGACCAGAAAGGAAAAUGUCUAGAGAUAGGAAGGUAAAUCAACUCUGCCAGCCCCUACCAUCAGGUCUGGGCCACCCCAAACUUGGGCUGCCUCCCUUAGACAUAGGUUAGAGUGAGAGACCCAGCUGUUUCUCCCGAAGCCUCGUCUUCAUGCCCCAGACACCUGAUUGCCCCAAUCAGGUGUCAGACUUGCUUGCUCUUCGAGGUCCCCCUGAGCUGCCAAGUGUUUUCAUUGUAAACAGACACAUCGCCAUGUUUCAGGGCUUCAACGGCAUUGUAUUUUGGACUUUGACCGUAUUUUUUUUCUCUUAACCUACUGAGACUCUUCCUUAAGAACAGGAUCUAUAGCUUUAAAAUGUCUUCUUCUAUGGGAAAUUUCCUGCCAAGCCAGGGCACUAAAUUCUUUCAUCAUUAGAGCUUUCCUGAAGUCCGGCCAUAUACUGAGUACCUGCUCUGAGUUCUGGGCAGCUUACAAUAUCUUAAACAGAUUUUCAGAAAAAUAAUGCAACUAUAUUUUCUAGUGUCAACUGUAUGCAAACAGUGUGGUAAAUACCUUUUAAUUAGUCCUCCACCCACCUGGAGUACAGGGGGUGCGUUUAUUAUUCUGAUUUCACUGAUGAGGAAAUGGGCUCAGAAAGGUUAAGUCCCUUCCUGAAAUCUCACAGCCAGGAGAAGCUAGGAUGAUUUAAAACAAAGUUUGGAGAGGCACUGGGCAUAGACCCUGGCUGUACAGCCUCUAACAUGCGGCACUGCAUCUUGGCAGUCUCUAUGCCUGUCUGUGAUGUGUGUGUGCACGUGUAACUACACACACACACACACACACACACACACACACACACAGCUAUCACACAUCUCAGAGCCUAAGAAAUAGGACUAAGCCCAGAACUCCUAGAAUCACCUAUAAAUGCUAGGCAUAGAUGGAAAUUAUUGUGUUCCACCAGAAGCACAGCUCCAAACUAUACCUAAAAAAUAUUUCUGCACUUCCCAGAGACCUGGACUUCAAACUUUCCCAGUGGAGCCUGAUUAUAGAACUUGAGGGUCCUAUCUCAGGAUGAAGGGGAGAGGCCCUGGCUUCACGGGAAGGUAUUCCAGCAUUGUUCUGCUUCACCCUUGACUGCGUUGUCUGGCAGUUUCUGUGUGCUGCCAGGAUAUUAUAUGGAACUGGAGAAGUUGGAGUCAGGUCUCUGAAGCUAGAGUUUCACUAAUUAGAUGCCUCUGUACAUGAGAACUAUUACUGUCUGCAGGUCCAUAUAGCUAAGCUGCCAGGAAAAACACAUUAUCUUCCAAAACUUUCAGAGCAUGUGCAGAACCCUUUCUUAGCGUUUUCUUCUCAGCAUUUUCUCUGCCUCCCAGAGGCUGGCAGCCAGUGACACUGCAGAGUUCAGCAUGUUCUAACCAUGCACGCAGGGCAGGGGCUGCCUUGGCCCUCCUCAGGCUUUCGUUGGGAGAGCAGGCAGUGGUGGAGCCCUUCUGGGUGCAGUCCUCUGGGGUUGCUCUUUGGAACUCAUGUAUGAGUUUGACUCCACAAGGCUUGGCAUGGAUACCAAAACAGUUGCAACAAAUUAGUUCUGAACCUGGAACAGAGAAUUCAGUGCUUCUGUUACUCAGGAAGGAGGUGUUCAGAAUGCCCCGUGCAGAGCAGCCAGUCAUUACUCUUGUUUGUUCUCACCUGGGUGCGCACCCUCAUGAUGCAGUGGCUGUAGCACCUUCAUGCCAGGUGCUGAGAGAAUGGGAAAUUCUUCCUCCCCAUUGACCUGAGUCCCAGAGACUUAGGGACACAGACUUCAGGUGAGGCUGCGGACCUCAGAAGCAGUGGAUAAUAGAUUGGGGCAUUAAAAGCUUUUGAGGCAGGGGGCUCAUGUUUUGACUGCAGGGAGUUAUGCUGAGCAAAGAGAUGUGUUUUUCAAAACCAGGGUUCAAAACCAGUGUCCACGCUGGAGUAAGUGGAGCAUGCUUCUCUGUGUUCUCUGAAUGAUCUUGCACUCCUCUUAAGCAAAGGAGUACCAUGACCAUAGUCAGUGGGAUCCCACAAAUGUUCUUAAAUGGGUAAGGCUUUAAGUAGCCAGAGAGUAUCCAGCCUACCAUUGGCUUCUCCACAUCCUAAAACCUGAGACAGCCUUGGUAUAUGCUUUAUAAAUGUUUCUUUUCUUGUUGUUUAAGUAAUUAAAGUGUUUAAAAUGUCUUCAUUAGAUGUGACGAUUGUUUAAUGAGUUUGCCUCUGACGUGUGGCUCCAUGGGAGAUAGGCAAAGUAAUUAAGAAGUUACCAGAAAUUGGUCGGCUGGGGAAAUGCAAAAGUUAGCAUUUCAGUAGUGAAUUUCUCCUGGAACAAAUGAGCAAUUUUUCCUCUUUCUCUUAAGUAGUAUACCCUUUUCUCACUUAGUAAUUUAAUGGUAUAUAAAGACAUGUGUAUAAGUGAGUGCAUACAUAUGAGGUAUGACUAUAGGGUUGUUUGUGGGAAUUUCUUUUCCUAACAUACAGAAGAUCAAAGUGUUCAUCUCACCCCGCCCUCCUUAAAAGGUGUCUUUUGGGAGACUAUGUGCUCAUUGACUAUAGUGCUGCCAAGUAAAAAUAUCUUGGGAACUCUUCUACUAGAAUGGCCUUCAGGGCUUGGCAUGUUCCUUUGGUUUACCCUUAGAGAUGAGAAAUCCUCCUCCUUUGAGGAUGGAUUUAAGUUCUGGAAAUAAUCUCAAGUGCUUGAUAGCACAGUUGGAUGAAAAAAGAUGGCAAUUAAGGUAAGUUACACCAUUUUUGUUUCUAAAAAAAUCCCUAAGAAAUUUCUUGGAAUGAGUCUUUGGCCUCAGAGCCUCUCAAAGUGUCCACUUCAAGGGGGGAUCAUCCUCAUUAGCACACAGAUUUUUAAAAAUCAAUUCUCUUGCCAUGCCUCCUAUGUGUUCACAUCUCUGCAUACACUACAGAUAUAAGUGCAUAAUCAUUCAUAUAAACAUCUGGUAGGUAUUCUGUAAAACUGUGUUUACUUUAGUGCAUGUUAUUGUCAUGUUAUGAUGUGACUGGGGUGUUUCUUUGUCAUGAAACUUUGCUUCUUCACAGAAUUAGAAUACUGCUCUCUCUAUAUUGAACUACAUAUACAGCGUUUUCUUGUAUCAGCCCCCAAAGUCUGGAUGCCCGGUGUUGUGUUUACAUGUGAUUGUGCCUAGGAGUCUGUUCACAUAGAGACACCUGUAAGUAUUUAUUACAAAACGGAAUGUAAGCAAAUAUAUCCACAUUGGUUUUAUUUGAAUCAAGGUGUUUUUUUGUUUUUUGUUUUUUUUCCUUUUGAGGAGGAACAGGGAGCCUCCUCCUCCAUGAGCACUUACAGAAUUGUGUAAAAUUCUGUGAAACAGUGGUAAGCAUGGGCACCCGAUUUCAGCUGUCCUGCUGCCGCUGCCCUCCAACCUGCUCUGUGUGUGUGUGUCGCUGUGCUUGGUGGCAGUGUGCCGUGCUCGUGCCGGCUCUUCCCAGCAGACUGGUAUCUGGCUGUAACGUUUGACGUCUUCAUAUUGCCAGUCUGUAUUGAGGGGUGAUGUACAUGGCCAUACAGCCAAAUGGGUCUGUGUACCAGUGUGGGGAUUCCAAGAACACUGCCUGUCCCCCACAGCAAAUAUUGAUGCUGUUGGUCAGCCAAAGAUUUUCCUCUCCUUUGCUGCUUAAACUUGUGCCUUAAUAUUGUACAUAAUAAAUGGAUAAAAUGGCAAAAUGACUCUUUUCUCUCGCUUGCUCCUUUCUUCCUUAAAGAACUUAUAAACUGAUGCUCAAUAAAUGUUUCAUUUCAUUGUA